GCCAGACUUAGCUGACCAGCCAGCAAGGACGCCCGCUGCCUCCCACCUGCCCUCCUGCCCUCCUUCACCAGCCAAGCCCAGCCUGAGCCAGCACCUGCCUUUAUGACCAUGUUCAAGGGACUGAGCAAAGGCUCCCAGGGGAAGGGGUCCCCCAAGGACUCCCCAGCCAAGGGGUCCCCCAAAGGCUCCCCCAGCAAGCACAGCUGAAUGCCACCCAGGAGCUGACCCUGCUCAUCUCCCACAUGCAAGCCAGCGCCGACCAGGUGGAGCGGGACAUCCUGGAGACGCAGAAGAGGCUGCAGCAGGACCGGCUGAACAGUGAGCAGAGCCAGGCCCUGCAGCACCAGCAGGAGACGGGCAGCAGCCUGAAGGAGGCCGAGGUGCUGCUCAAGGACCUCUUCCUGGACGUGGACAAGGCCCGGCGGCUCAAGCACCCGCAGGCUGAGGAGACUGAGAAGGACAUCGAGCAGCUGCACGAGCGGGUGACCCAGGAGUGUGCGGAGUACUGUGCCCUGUACGAGAAGAUGGUGCUGCCGCCCCGACGUGGGAUCCAAGGUCGACUGGGCACACGUGCUGGAGCAGAAACAGAAGCUGGUCUGCGCAGGCCAGUAUGGGCCGGGCAUGGCGGAGCUGGAGGAACAGAUCGCGGAGCUCAACAUCGUGCAGAAGGAGAUCAACGACCAAGGAGAGCAGCUGCGGAGCCUGGUGGGGCCGGAUGCCGCCACCAUCCGGAGCCAAUACCGAGACCUACUGAGGGCGGCGUCGUGGCGCGGGCAGAGCCUGGGCAGCCUGUACACGCACUGCAGGGCUGCACGUGGCAGCUGAGCGCCCUGGCGGAGCAGCAGCGCCGCAUCCUGCAGCAGGACUGGAGCGACCUCAUGGCCGACCCUGCGGGCGUGCGGCGGGAAUACGAGCACUUCAAGCAGCACGAGCUGCUGAGCCAGGAGCAGAGCGUAAACCAGCUGGAGGAGGACGGCAAGCGCAUGGUGGAGCUGCGGCACCCCGCGGUGGGGCCCAUCCAGGCCCACCAGGAGGCCCUGAAGAUGGAGUGGCAGAACUUCCUGAACCUGUGCAUCUGCCAGGAGACCCAGCUCCAGCACGUGGAGGACUACAGCCGGAUUCUGUGUCCAUCUUCCUCUCCUCAUUGACUCUGCAUGAAGGGGAUUUCUGGUGGAGUAAGGGUAGCAGGUGAGAAAUGAAGUACCAAGAAACUAGCAAAGGGUCUUCUGGUUGUCUGGGGACAGUCCUCCUGUCAUCCCCAGCCUAGUCUCAAGGGUUCUGGGCCGGUCACCCUGCUGCCUCUGUGCUGUGUCUCUGGAUCUGGCCUCCAUGGGAAGGACCCUGGGAGACCCAGCAGAGUGGGGUACCUGGGUUGACAAACAGCUUCCUGUUCCUCUGGCUAUGUGGCUCAGGAAUAGGCCCAGACAGUGCAUCCAGAUGUGUGAGGCCACAUCACUGCCCCCUUUGAGAUGGCCCAGAGGACCUUGUGGCACAAGCGUGAAGCUCAGCACCCGGAGCCUGGGACAAACUGCCCCUCCCUGUGUCCUGGAGUUGGGGUCCGGUCCCGAGAAGACUCUCAGUCACCUGUGGGUGCUGAUGAGGGGAGGGAGAGGUCUGUGGACUGAGAAGGGCCAUUGGUAGGGGACUCUGAACACCACCGCUCAGGGGUCUGGUCAGUGGGGGUCUGGUCAGCAGAGAUUGAACUCUGGGGCUCAGACACAGAAAACCUGCUCAGUGACCCUUUCUCCUUUUUCAGCUCUUGCCGCACGUGCAGAGAGAGAGGAACUUCCAGUGCCCGCUAUGGAGCCACAGCCCACAGCAUGGGGAAGUCCCCAUCCAGAGGCAGUGCUGCAGCUAGAGGUAGCUCCAGAGUCCUCCGGGCCCUGCACCGAUACAGCCAAAGACCAGCAAAGCGACAAGCUGCCAGACCUCAUGCCACCUGCUGUAGCCACUGGGCUCAGCCCUGGAGCUGAGAGCAUCGCUGGAGAUAGACGUGGCAGAGAAGAGGUUGCGAGCAUGGCCCCAGCCAGCAGCUCCCACGCUGCCCCUAGUCCUGGGCAUGGAGCGAGCCUUGGUGUCAGAGACCAGGGUGUGCAGUCUGAGCUCCUCUACCUUACUAAAGAGAGGCCUCUUUUAUUUACCAGAGCCACAGCCCUGCUGCCUCAGGACCUUUUCAUUCUGCCGGUGCUGGGGCUGUCUAUCUGCAAGCUGGAGGUGUUGAGAGCAGGAAAAGGAGGCUGUGAGGAAGGGUUCGGGCAGCUCCUCCUGCUCUCAGAGGUGGCCUCCUCCUCCAGGCAUGGAGGUCUGUCCACUACUGGGCUUCUGGGCUAUUUGCCCCUGAUUUGCUCCCUGGUACGGGCUCUUCUUAACAGGCAGGCAAGGGGUGCGGGGACCAGGUGAGGGCUUCAAAGGGUACAGUACCAAAUCUUCCAAACUCAGCACUUGUGCCCUGGGGUCUCCAAACUGUCUUCUGCCCUAGAAUUUAUUCAUACUGUUAAAUUACCAGUUUAUGCAAAUGAUAUGUAAAUAAAGCUCAAUUUUUUGAAACUUCA